AGAACCCGGAAGUGCGAGGCCGAGGAGAGCCACGUGGGUCGAGCUGGGGCGCAGCUCGCAUGGGGGAGUCUAUCCCGCUGGCCGCCCCGGUCCCGGUGGAACAGGCGGUGCUGGAGACGUUCUUCUCUCACCUGGGUAUCUUCUCUUACGACAAGGCUAAGGACAAUGUGGAGAAGGAACGAGAGGCCAACAAGAGCGCGGGGGGCAGCUGGCUGUCGCUGCUGGCGGCCUUGGCGCACCUGGCCGCGGCCGAGAAGGUCUAUCACAGCCUCACCUACCUGGGGCAGAAACUAGGGGGCCAGUCUUUCUUCAGCAGGAAGGAUUCCAUCCGCACCAUCUAUACUUCAUUGCAUAAUGAGCUGAAGAAGGUGGUGACUGGCCGUGGUGCCCUGGGUGGGACUGCUCCUCACGUGGAAGAACUCCUUUCCCACCUGUCAGAGCAGCUCUGCUUCUUUGUUCAGGCUCGGAUGGAGAUAGCAGACUUCUAUGAGAAGAUGUACACCCUCAGCACACAGAAGUUCAUCAAUGCUGAAGAGCUCGUUGGCCUUUUGGAUGCCAUCAUGAAAAAAUACAGCUCCAGAUUUCACCACCCAAUCCUCAGUCCUUUGGAAAGCAGUUUCCAGCUGGAAGUUGACGUCCUGUGUCAUCUCCUGAAAGCCCAGGCCCAGGUCUCAGAGUGGAAGUUCCUCCCAUCUCUGGUUAAUUUACACAGUGCGCACACCAAACUGCAGACGUGGGGCCAGAUCUUUGAGAAACAGCGGGAGACCAAGAAACAUCUGUUUGGAGGGCAGUCUCAGAAGGCCGUGCAGCCUCCACACCUUUUCCUUUGGCUGAUGAAACUCAAAAACAUGCUUCUUGCCAAGUUUAGCUUUUACUUUCAUGAGGCUCUGAGCCGACAAACGACUGCUUCAGAAAUGAAAACGUUGACAGCAAAAGCUAACCCAGACUUUUUUGGAAAGAUUUCCAGCUUCAUCAGAAAAUAUGAUGCUGCCAAUGUGUCCUUAAUUUUUGACAACAGAGGUUCUGAGAGUUUUCAGGGUCAUGGUUAUCACCACCCCCAUUCCUACAGAGAGGCCCCCAAGGGUGUGGACCAGUAUCCAGCUGUAGUGUCUCUGCCCAGCGACAGGCCAGUCAUGCACUGGCCCAAUGUCAUCAUGAUCAUGACGGACCGCACAUCUGAUCUGAACAGCUUGGAGAAAGUGGUCCACUUCUAUGAUGACAAAGUUCAGAGUACCUACUUCCUAACCCGCCCGGAACCUCACUUUACCAUUGUCAUCAUUUUUGAGUCAAAGAAAUCUGAGAGAGACUCCCACUUUAUUUCCUUCCUCAAUGAGGUCUCACUUGCCCUUAAGAACCCCAAAGUGUUUGCAAGUCUGAAACCUGGAGCCAAAGGUUAGCAGGUGAUUUGCGUGGAGGGGUUUCAAGACUAGAAACUGUUCUUAAUUGCCCUAAUGAUCUACGGUGGUCUGUGAAUAGAGUUUACAUCCAUUCAUGCCUCUUUCAGAACUAAAUUAAAGACAAAUCCUCCCUGUGUUGCACACUUUAUAAGCAAUUAAGGCCAAUUGAAUUAAGUUUCCAAAGAGUAAUCUAGGAAGUGGUCAUGGGCUACCAUGUGUCUCCAUGGUACAGCAAAGUAGUUUCAGUAUUUUCCCCUAUUUUGCUAUAUUUCUUGUAGAUUGAAUAUUUAUUGGGCUUUUUUUUUUCCCAUAUGUUUUUCUGUUGUUCUAAACAUUGUGUUCUACUGCAAUUCCAAACAGCCUCUCUGUUUCCCUCCUUCUUGGAAGAGUAAUAGGGAUGAGAUAUUAAAUGGCCUUUUUAGAAUUAAGAACUAUAUGUUUUCUGUCUCAUAAAUUAGCAAAUGAAUAUGGAGUUAGUAGAUUUAUGAUUCUGAUCUACAAAUUAACAUUUUUGAUGCCAAAAUUAGGGUCUUGGUAAGAAAUUUCUAUCAGUUAUUGAAACUGAAAGUGAGUCAGAUUGGUAGCAUGACGUAAGGUUUUAACAGUUCAGAAGAUCCUCAUGGCAGCUUUAAUAGCCAUGGGUUCUUUUGGGGUAAUGUACACACCUAACUGCAUUUGUUUUGACUUCUUUAAUGUUUGAAUGUUUCACUCUGUUGUAAAGUCAGCAUAAGCCAUCAUGUGGGCUUUCUUCAUUCUUCAGCAUAUUAUCCGCUUCGCUUUCUGUUUAUCACUUUUCUGCUGAAAUGUACAUGUUUGGCUCUACUCCUUGGUUAUUUUUAGGCUUAAAAGCAUGCAGUCGGUUUUUCAGCCACUUUUAGAUACUCAUGCAACAUAGCCUACUUUUAUAAAAUCAAAAUGAAGGUCUUCAUACGCUGUACUUGCUAAAAAUCAACUGUGCGCUUGAAAGACCUCUUCAUAGUUGAGUAAUCACCUCAGUACUUAAGCACUUCUGAACUUGGGUUUCAUGCCUGCCCCCCACAAAUUAUGUUUAGAAGCAGCACUGCAUCUUAGCACAUGCUGCCUUAUUUCUUUCCUUCGGCAGGUGUUCAUGGGAAGUAGGUGGAUCAGUGAAGGCAUAAUGGGCUGUGGAGACCUUCACUUCUAGAUUAUUGAUUCAAAAUAAAAAGAAGCCACAAAGAGUAAUUGAGUUGUUACUGGUUUGAUGGUUCCUUUGAAGCUUGUGUGAAAUGUAAUGGUCAUAUUCGUCUUUUUUCCCAUGAUUGUGUGGAGCCACUGUUUUACUGGGUGUCCACAGCAGGUAUGCCAGCAACAUCAGCAGAGACCAGAGAGCCCCUCAGAGUCCAUGUAGGAAGCCUGCCCACCUAGGGUGGACUGCCUGGCAGAAGAAAGAAGAACCGGCCAGGCACGGUGGCACACGCCUGUAAUCCCAGUACUUUGGGAGGCUGAGACGCGUGGAUCACUUGAGGUCAGGAGUUCGAGAUCAGCGUGGCCAACAUGGUGAAACCCCAUCUCUACUAAAAAUACAAAAGUUGGCCGGUUGUAGUGACGGGUGACUGUAAUCCCAGUUACUCUGGAGGCUGAGGCAGGAGAAUUGCUUGAACCUGGGAGGUGGAGGAUGCAGUGAGCUGAGACUGUGCAGCUGCACUCCAGCCUGGGUGAAAGAGCGAGACCUGUCUCAAAAAAAAAAAAAGAAGAAGAAGAACCAAGAAUCUACUGGCCUAUUUUUUAUUUUCUGGGAAGAACAUGUGUUUUUCCUUUUUUUUUUUUUUUUUUUUUGAGACAGGGUCUUGUCUGUUUUCCAGGCUGGAGUACAGUGGCACAAUCACAACUCACUGCAGCCUCAACCUCCUGGGCUCAAGUGAUCCUCCCACAUCAGCAUCCCGAGUAGGUGGGAUUACAGGCAUGAGCCAUCACACCUGGGUCUCACUAUGUUGCUCGGGCUGGACUCAAACUCCUGGACUCACAUGAGCCUCCCGCCUCGGCCUCCCAAAGCACUGGGUUUAUAAGCAUGUGCCACUGCACCUGGCCUCCUUUCUUUUUCUUUAAAAAUGGUCAUAAGCUUUGUAAAAAGCUAGUUUGCUUUAAAUAGAAAGUAGUGAUUUACCUCUGCAUUUUAUUCACUCAGGUUCUAUAAAAAAAGUCUCAGCAGAUUUUACAACAUUGACCUUACCUAAGAAAUUGAAAGCAAUUGGAGCUAAAAAGUCAAAUCACUUUUCCUCUCUAUUGUGUUCUGCCAAGAAACUGAAAAAUAUUCCUUGGUAUGCAUGUAUUUUUUUCCUCUUAGAUUAAACCACCAUUAGCCUUAAUGACACAGUCCCCCAAAUACCUAGAAGAAUAUAUACUUCAGUGGAACCCCGAGAGAGGUGUAAGUAAAGCAUAUAUAUGUUAUUUAAAUAACCAGUCCUCACCUAGAACAUAUUUGAAUUGUAUAUCUAUUUUUAAACAUAAACACAAAAAGAAUUUCAAAGAACAGAAGGCAGAUGUGAAUAUUAAGAAAAUCUAAGACAAUAUGUAUUACUGUGCAGCUGUCAUAGACUGUACUGGAAGAGUUUUUGAAGAUUGAAUAUUGAUACUUAAAUUAUUUCUGAAGCUCUUCAAUAAAGUUUUCUAAUUAUAAAAACUCCACAUAAUUUGGUUCAAGCCAAGAAACAAAGUCAUUUUACUCUAAGAUUUAUUCUCUAAAUAUAGUAAUGAGAUCUGUAAAGUCUGUGUUUUGCUAAUUAAAAGAGUAAAUCUGCGUA